GUGCCUUCCAAGCGCCCAGAGGCCAACGGUCCCCCAGCCAUGGGCGCUGCAGCUCCGGCCGAGUCCGCAGACCUCGGGAACUUCUGGAAGGCGGGAGAACCCCUGCUGCAAGGCCCCGACGCCCUGGCGGCUCCCAUGAGCAGGUCACCCAGCACGCCCCAGACCACGCCAUCUCCCCAGGGUCGCCAGAGUCCCUGGCCCCUGAGGUCCCUGACUCAGAGCCAUAUUCAGUACUUCCAGUGGGGGCGCCCGGUGCCCAGCACCCACCUCAUCGAGGUGCGGCCCACCCAGGACCCCGCCAAGCCGCAGCGGGUGGUCUCCGAGGGCUGGAGGCGCCCUGCCCUUCCCGGGGAGACCGCUCUGGGGCGAGACCUCUCCUGUGCCUGGGAGGGUUGCAUGAAAGGGGGGCUGUGUCGUGCCUGGAACCCAGGACGGACCUGGAGCCCGGUGACCAUCGGGAUCGCGCCCCCUGAGCGUCAGGAGAGCCCCUGGAGAUCCCCUGGACAGAGAGCCCGCCCCGCAGGCCGCCCCGCCGCCCAGGAGCUCCUGGACCCCUGCACCCGGGAGACUCUGCUGGGGGCGCUCAGCCAGUGCCCCAAGGGAAGCGCUAGGUUCGACGGGCCGUUGUGGUUCGAGGUCUCAGACAGCAAGGGUGGCAGGCGGAACCUGCAGCCCCGGCCCUCUGCCUUCAAGCCCCUGAGCAAAAAUGGAGCGGUUGCUUCCUUCGUGCCCAGGCCAGGGCCUCUGAAGCCGAGCCUCGGCCCCUGGAGCCUCAGUUUUUGUGAUGAUGCUUGGCCUUCCGUGCUGGUCCAGCCCGCCCCAUCCGCCAUCUGGGACUUCUGGGAGGCGACAACGCCUUCCUGCGGCAGCUGCAGUAGGGUCUCCUUCGCCCUCGAGGUCACCCAGUCUGCUGGCCCCUUUGGCUCCUAAGAAUCUGGGCUCUGCUACCCACCUCCGGAGACACAAGCCCACGUAUCUACUUUCACUUGCUCAUCCUUGCUCUACCUCAACGUGGGGCCCUGACACCACGUUAUCAAACAUGCAGCCCCCACACCCCUCGUCUGCCCGCCCCCAGAUCUUCCCUCUGUGCUCCCUGCCACCCCAGCAGCUGUUGAUUUCAGAACCCUUGCCUUCGCCCUGCUGGCCCUCUCCUCCCUGCCCUUCUUCCUGCCCUUCCUCUGAAAAGAGGCAUUUCGGGAAGGCUUGCUUUUUCUCCAUGUCUCCCAGUUUGUAUAGUUAAAUUGUCCAGUUGUAUAGUUAAAUAUUUGAUCUUAUUAAAAACAUUUGUCUGCA